GUUCCGCAUUCUGCAAGCCUCCGGAGCGCACGUCGGCAGUCGGCUCCCUCGUUGACCGAAUCACCGACCUCUCUCCCCAGCUGUAUUUCCAAAAUGUCGCUUUCUAACAAGCUGACGCUGGACAAGCUGGACGUUAAAGGGAAGCGGGUCGUUAUGAGAGUCGACUUCAAUGUUCCUAUGAAGAACAACCAGAUAACAAACAACCAGAGGAUUAAGGCUGCUGUCCCAAGCAUCAAAUUCUGCUUGGACAAUGGAGCCAAGUCGGUAGUCCUUAUGAGCCACCUAGGCCGGCCUGAUGGUGUGCCCAUGCCUGACAAGUACUCCUUAGAGCCAGUUGCUGUAGAACUCAAAUCUCUGCUGGGCAAGGAUGUUCUGUUCUUGAAGGACUGUGUAGGCCCAGAAGUGGAGAAAGCCUGUGCCAACCCAGCUGCUGGGUCUGUCAUCCUGCUGGAGAACCUCCGCUUUCAUGUGGAGGAAGAAGGGAAGGGAAAAGAUGCUUCUGGGAACAAGGUUAAAGCCGAGCCAGCCAAAAUAGAAGCUUUCCGAGCUUCACUUUCCAAGCUAGGGGAUGUCUAUGUCAAUGAUGCUUUUGGCACUGCUCACAGAGCCCACAGCUCCAUGGUAGGAGUCAAUCUGCCACAGAAGGCUGGUGGGUUUUUGAUGAAGAAGGAGCUGAACUACUUUGCAAAGGCCUUGGAGAGCCCAGAGCGACCCUUCCUGGCCAUCCUGGGCGGAGCUAAAGUUGCAGACAAGAUCCAGCUCAUCAAUAAUAUGCUGGACAAAGUCAAUGAGAUGAUUAUUGGUGGUGGAAUGGCUUUUACCUUCCUUAAGGUGCUCAACAACAUGGAGAUUGGCACUUCUCUGUUUGAUGAAGAGGGAGCCAAGAUUGUCAAAGACCUAAUGUCCAAAGCUGAGAAGAAUGGUGUGAAGAUUACCUUGCCUGUUGACUUUGUCACUGCUGACAAGUUUGAUGAGAAUGCCAAGACUGGCCAAGCCACUGUGGCUUCUGGCAUACCUGCUGGCUGGAUGGGCUUGGACUGUGGUCCUGAAAGCAGCAAGAAGUAUGCUGAGGCUGUCACUCGGGCUAAGCAGAUUGUGUGGAAUGGUCCUGUGGGGGUAUUUGAAUGGGAAGCUUUUGCCCGGGGAACCAAAGCUCUCAUGGAUGAGGUGGUGAAAGCCACUUCUAGGGGCUGCAUCACCAUCAUAGGUGGUGGAGACACUGCCACUUGCUGUGCCAAAUGGAACACGGAGGAUAAAGUCAGCCAUGUGAGCACUGGGGGUGGUGCCAGUUUGGAGCUCCUGGAAGGUAAAGUCCUUCCUGGGGUGGAUGCUCUCAGCAAUAUUUAGUACUUUCCUGCCUUUUAGUUCCUGUGCACAGCCCCUAAGUCAACUUAGCAUUUUCUGCAUCUCCACUUGGCAUUAGCUAAAACCUUCCAUGUCAAGAUUCAGCUAGUGGCCAAGAGAUGCAGUGCCAGGAACCCUUAAACAGUUGCACAGCAUCUCAGCUCAUCUUCACUGCACCCUGGAUUUGCAUACAUUCUUCAAGAUCCCAUUUGAAUUUUUUAGUGACUAAACCAUUGUGCAUUCUAGAGUGCAUAUAUUUAUAUUUUGCCUGUUAAAAAGAAAGUGAGCAGUGUUAGCUUAGUUCUCUUUUGAUGUAGGUUAUUAUGAUUAGCUUUGUCACUGUUUCACUACUCAGCAUGGAAACAAGAUGAAAUUCCAUUUGUAGGUAGUGAGACAAAAUUGAUGAUCCAUUAAGUAAACAAUAAAAGUGUCCAUUGAAACCGUGAUUUUUUUUUUUUUCCUGUCAUACUUUGUUAGGAAGGGUGAGAAUAGAAUCUUGAGGAACGGAUCAGAUGUCUAUAUUGCUGAAUGCAAGAAGUGGGGCAGCAGCAGUGGAGAGAUGGGACAAUUAGAUAAAUGUCCAUUCUUUAUCAAGGGCCUACUUUAUGGCAGACAUUGUGCUAGUGCUUUUAUUCUAACUUUUAUUUUUAUCAGUUACACAUGAUCAUAAUUUAAAAAGUCAAGGCUUAUAACAAAAAAGCCCCAGCCCAUUCCUCCCAUUCAAGAUUCCCACUCCCCAGAGGUGACCACUUUCAACUCUUGAGUUUUUCAGGUAUAUACCUCCAUGUUUCUAAGUAAUAUGCUUAUAUUGUUCACUUCUUUUUUUUUUAUUUUUUAAAGAAAUCUAUUUCAUACCAUGGAGGAAGGCUCUGUUCCACAUAUAUUUCCACUUCUUCAUUCUCUCGGUAUAGUUUUGUCACAAUUAUAGAUUAGAUCAAAAGUCUACAUAACUAAUACAGCUGAGCUAUGUAGUAUGCUAUGAUUAAAUUUACUUAUGUAACUUUUAUUGUCUUUGGCAUUAACAGUGUUUCAAAAAAUUUUCUGUGUAUACCCAUCAGUGAUUCAUUCCCAAAUCUUCUAGAAGCAUAAGUGUCUCAAUAUAUUAAAACAUAUUGAAUAAUCCUUGUUAGAGUUAUCCCUGCAGGAGUCCUUAGUGCUCCUUUAUCCAAUUUGUACUUGAUGCCCUCUAGGCAGGGUGUACAGCUAGCUGUUGCUCUGGUAUUUCCUAUAACCUUCUUGGGGAUUUCUUUUACCUCCUGUGUUAGACUCCUGUUUUCUGGAUUCCCCCUUUUCCCUCUUUCUUGGUCUACUUUUUGUAGAACACAAGACUCUACUAGCUUCCUGAGAAAGGGUGCCUGGGAGGCAAAAUCUCUAAGACUUUGUAAGUCUGAAAAUGUCUUUAUUCGACCCUUAUACUUGAUUCCUAGUUUGGCUAUAUAUAGAAUUUUAGCCUGAGUAUCACUUUUUGAGACUCGAAGCCACUGUUUCAUUGUCACUAUUGAGAAUCUAAAUGGCCAUUCGGAUUCUUUCAUCAUCUUUAUAAUUUUACCUUCCUAUUUCUUUCCUGUCCUUUUAAUGGAGUUUUGGGAGAGAGCAGAGGUAAACAUGAUUUGAAAAAGCCAUGUCUGACCAGAAAUUCUGUGCUGGAAAGAUAUGUAUUUCACCUUUAGGGACAAAGAAAUAAACUUUUGGACAGGACCACAGAGCUAGUAAGUAACAGCAGGGAUUCAAGUCCAGGUUUGUCUGGUUCCAGUGGCUGAUGCUUUUCCAAUGUGCCUCCGUCCCUGACAUGAUGCUUCUAGGCUAUAGAUGCUUCUAGACUCUAUCCCUGACAUGAUGCUUCUAGACUAUUUUGUUUAACCCUGGAUAGAAUAGCAAAAGAAAAUUUUGGUGGUUGCUCUAAACAAAACAGAAAUUUGAAAGCUCAAGUUUUUUCUUCAUUUGUAUUUUAGUUAAUACUGUACCCAUAUUUGUAGUUAAUUUUAAAUUGUACCAUGUUUCUGCAUACCUCUAUGGGUACUCAGGAAUUCUAGUCCAAUUUUUGUGACUUUUUCCUACUGAUUACCUUUCCUCCAACGUUUUAAAAAUUAUUUCAAAUGGAACUGAAAGAAGCAUAAACUCCCAUAAACCCAGCACCUAGACUCUACAAUUGCCAACAUUAUCUAUCCAACAAUCUCUGACUGUACCUUUUAAGUACUUUCUACUGGACUGUUUCCAGGAUCACCCCUCAUUUAUUUGGGUUGUUAACCUAAAGAAUGAAUGGGGGAAUCUCCAGUCAUAAACAACUUGUCAAUUAGGCAAAUAUUUGAGUUCCUUCUAUGUGCUUAAAGACGUGAUAGAGGGAAUAUAAGAGCAUUUAUGUUCUGAAGGAAUUUUUAACCUAACCAAAGAAGAUAGUAGAUAACUUGUGUGCAUAUAAGCUAGAACAGUAUAAGGGGCCGGGCAUGGUGGCUUACGCCUGUAAUCCCAGGACUUUGGGAGGCCAAGGCGGGCAGAUCACCUGUCAGGAGUUUGGGACCAGCCUGGCCAACAUGGUGAAACCCCGUUUCUACCAAAAAUACAAAAAUUAGCCGGGCGUGGUGGCGUGUGCCACUGUAGUCCCAGCUAUUCAGAAGGCUGAGGCAGGAGAAUCACUUGAACCCGGGAGGUGGAGGUUGCAGUGAGCUGAGAUCACGCUACUGCAUUCCUGCUUGGGCGACAGAGUGAGACUCUGCCUCAAAACAAAAACCCCACAAAACAGUAUAAGGAUGUGCUUUCUAAUUUGGAAUUAUGAAUUAUUGGUAAAAUAUUGCAAAGGUGUAUGCUUUAAGUUGUAAAUUCACCUUUAACCCUAGACUAUAUAUGUGUGUUUAUAUGCAGAAAAAAAUAAUUCCCAUGUCGUAAGUGAACAAUUUGGUUCUUUAGCUCAGUGUUUUCCUGUUUUCUUCAUUUCCAAAAUUUCCCUCUAGCACAGGGGUUUACACAUGAUCAAAAAGGAGUAUACAAUGAAGACACCUUCCUCAGUCCCCUACCUACCAGUUUCCCUCCCCAGAAGCAACCUCUGGAAGACCAGUUUCUUUCAAUCUAAGGCUAUUUAAUAUACAUUAAGAGGCCGGGCGCAGUGGCUCACGCCUGUAAUCCCAACAACACUUUGGGAGGCCCAGGCAGGCGGGUCAUGAGGUCAGGAGAUUGAGACCAUCCUGGCUAACACGGUGAAACCCUGUCUCUACUAAAAAUACAAAAAAUUAGCUGGGCGUGAUGGUGGGCGCCUGUAGUCCCAGCUACUCGGGAGGCUGAGGCAGGAGAAUGGCGUGAACCUGGGAAGCGGAGCUCGCAGUGAGCCGAGAUCACGCCACUGCACUCCAGCCUGGGCAACAGUGAGACUCUGCAUAAAGAGCAUACCCAUGUGUGUACCUAUCUAUCUAUCUAUCUAUCUAUCUAUCUAUCUAUCUAUCUGUAUAUAGAUAUAUUAAAAUGUAAAUGGUGGCA